GGAGACCGCUUCACCCUGAUCAGGGAGUAUCGGCUGCGGGUGCGCAAGGCGUCCAGGAGUGACCUGGGGCUGUGGAGAGCGACCCGUGGCCUUGUGUUUCAGGUACGGAGGUUCCGGACUGGACGGGCGUCAGGAAGUCACAGACUUGUCCUCUGAUGUGGCCCCGCCCGCCGCCGCACUAAUCUCUUCGGCGUCGUACCCGUCGGCCCAGCUCGACCCGCCGCAGCCCCGGCCCCGACCGUGGACACUGGGGGUCCCCGAGGGCGCUGCGACCUCCUCCCGGGUGAAAUGAAACCCGAGGGCAGUCCCCCUUACCGACCCCAUUAGAGACGUAUCUGCCGUGCCAGGGGUCUAGGCUCCAGAAACAGGGAGUUUACCACCUAGGAUGACUUCAGUGACUAGAUCAGAGAUCAUAGAUGAAAAAGGACCAGUGAUGUCUAAGACUCAUGAUCAUCAAUUGGAAUCAAGUCUCAGUCCUGUGGAAGUGUUUGCUAAAACAUCUGCCUCCCUGGAGAUGAAUCAAGGCGUUUCAGAGGAAAGAAUUCACCUUGGCUCUAGCCCUAAAAAAGGGGGAAAUUGUGAUCUCAGCCACCAGGAAAGACUUCAGUCGAAGUCCCUUCAUUUGUCUCCUCAAGAACAAUCUGCCAGUUAUCAAGACAGGAGGCAAUCCUGGCGGCGAGCAAGUAUGAAAGAAACGAACCGGCGGAAGUCGCUGCAUCCCAUUCACCAGGGCAUCACAGAGCUCAGCCGGUCUAUCAGUGUCGAUUUAGCAGAAAGCAAACGGCUUGGCUGUCUCCUGCUUUCCAGUUUCCAGUUCUCUAUUCAGAAACUUGAACCUUUCCUAAGGGACACUAAGGGCUUCAGUCUUGAAAGUUUUAGAGCCAAAGCAUCUUCUCUUUCUGAAGAAUUGAAACAUUUUGCAGACGGACUGGAAACUGAUGGAACUCUACAAAAAUGUUUUGAAGAUUCAAAUGGAAAAGCAUCAGAUUUUUCUUUGGAAGCAUCUGUGGCUGAGAUGAAGGAAUACAUAACAAAGUUUUCUUUAGAACGUCAGACUUGGGAUCAGCUCUUGCUUCACUACCAGCAGGAGGCUAAAGAGAUAUUGUCCAGAGGAUCAACUGAGGCCAAAAUUACUGAGGUCAAAGUGGAACCUAUGACAUAUCUUGGGUCUUCUCAGAAUGAAGUUCUUAAUACAAAACCUGACUACCAGAAAAUAUUACAGAACCAGAGCAAAGUCUUUGACUGUAUGGAGUUGGUGAUGGAUGAACUGCAAGGAUCAGUGAAACAGCUGCAGGCCUUUAUGGAUGAAAGUACCCAGUGCUUCCAGAAGGUGUCAGUACAGCUCGGAAAGAGAAGCAUGCAACAAUUAGAUCCCUCACCAGCUCGAAAACUGUUGAAGCUUCAGCUACAGAACCCACCUGCCAUACAUGGAUCUGGAUCUGGAUCUUGUCAGUGACUUUAUGAGAGUUUCUGCCACAAGGUGCCCAAGAGGAGAGGAAUGGGAAGAGUGCCCCAGCACGUGGUGACUGCGUGAUUUCUGCUCGUUGCCUUUGAAGAUAACUGGCAGGACUGACUGUAGAACACUUUGACUUUUUUCAAAAAGUGAUGGAAUUUGUACAUCCAAAUGAAUAUUGUAUAGACAAUUUUCCCAGGAAUGUGCAAAAUGCUUGAAAGUUCAAACUUCUUUUUUGAAAUGAUCUUCAGAUCCAGUGGCCCAUUCUUUUAUCUUUAUCCUGUGAAGGUGUUUUUCAGGUUUUGAAACAAUCCAAAAAUCAUUUAGGACCAAGUCUAAGGAAACAUUUUAGUGGCCAAGUUGGAUUCCGAUUGUAAAGGAAUGAUACUAAUUUUCUAGCAUGGCUCUGAAGGUGAUUUUAGGUAGAAGAGUUUUGAGGCUGGGCGCAAUGGCUCACGCCUGUAAUCCUAGCAUUUUGGGUGACUGAGGCGGGUGGAUUGCUUGAGCCCAGAAGUUGAAGACCAGCCUGAGAAAUAAGGUGAAACCCUGUCUACAAAAAAUACAAAAAGUUAGCUGGGUGUGGUGGCGUGUGCCUGUAGUGCUAGCUACUCAGAAGGCUGAGGUGGGAGGAUUGUUUGAGCCCAGGAGGUUGAGGCUGCAGUGAGUUCUAAUUGCGCCACUGCACUCCAGCCUGAGCGACAGAGUGAGACACUGUCUUAAAAAAAAUUAAAAAUUGUAAAAAAAUGAAAAAAAAAGUUUUGAGCAUUAUUUGCAUCAUUGGGAUACAUAUGUCACUUCACAAGAUGUUCAAUUUGAAGGAAAUACCACUCAUUCUCUAUGUCCUGUUGUCUGUAGUGUGCUUCAGUUUUUCAUAUUGAGUUGACCUAAAUCCUGGAUUCAUGACAAGAAAGGAGUAAGUACUACUAUUCAUUGUUCUAUUUGUUUAUAAUCUGUAUUAUAAAAUUGCACAUAAUUAAAAGCUUUCCCUUGUCUUCA